GAGAGAGAAGCUGGGAGAGCAGAGAAAAGGGGCCACCGGUCGCCCCCCCGCUUCCCCGCACGCGCUCUCCAGCCGCGGCCGCCCGCCUGCCGCGGUCACCCCGGCCUCUGCCUCUGUCCCCCAGUGAUCGGAUCAAGGCGCUGAGCGAGGCCCUGCCUGCGGGGCGGCCAUGCGGCGGUGACAGGAGCGCGACCGACACGCACGGGCCCCUCGCCCCCUCUCGCCUCCCGUCCGCUCGCCAGCUCCCCUCAGCCGAGGCUGCUCCGCGGCGGCCGCAGCCCGCGCGCGGCCCACACUCGCCUCCCCUCGGCACCCCCGGCCCCGGAGCUGCCUGGAGGCGGCCGCACUCGGGGAUCAUGGCCCAAGUUGCAAUGUCCACCCUCCCCGUUGAAGAUGAGGAGUCCUCGGAGAGCAGGAUGGUGGUGACAUUCCUCAUGUCAGCUCUCGAGUCCAUGUGUAAAGAACUGGCCAAGUCCAAAGCCGAAGUGGCCUGCAUUGCAGUGUAUGAAACAGACGUGUUUGUCGUCGGAACUGAAAGAGGACGUGCUUUUGUCAAUACCAGAAAGGAUUUUCAAAAAGAUUUUGUAAAAUAUUGUGUUGAAGAAGAAGAAAAAGCUGCAGAGAUGCAUAAAAUGAAAUCUACAACCCAGGCAAAUCGGAUGAGUGUAGAUGCUGUAGAAAUUGAAACACUCAGAAAAACAGUUGAGGACUAUUUCUGCUUUUGCUAUGGGAAAGCUUUAGGCAAAUCCACAGUGGUACCUGUACCAUAUGAGAAGAUGCUGCGAGACCAGUCGGCUGUGGUAGUGCAGGGGCUUCCGGAAGGUGUUGCCUUUAAACACCCCGAGAACUAUGAUCUUGCAACCCUGAAAUGGAUUUUGGAGAACAAAGCAGGGAUUUCAUUCAUCAUUAAGAGACCUUUUUUAGAGCCAAAGAAGCAUGUAGGUGGUCGUGUGAUGGUAACAGAUGCUGACAGGUCAAUACUAUCUCCAGGUGGAAGUUGUGGCCCCAUCAAAGUGAAAACUGAACCCACAGAAGAUUCUGGCAUUUCCCUGGAAAUGGCAGCUGUGACAGUAAAGGAAGAAUCAGAAGAUCCUGAUUAUUAUCAAUAUAACAUUCAAGCAGGCCCUUCUGAAACUGAUGAUGUUGAUGAAAAACAGCCCCUAUCGAAGCCUUUGCAAGGAAGCCACCAUUCUUCAGAGGGCAAUGAAGGCACAGAAAUGGAAGUACCAGCAGAAGAUUCUACUCAACAUGUCCCUUCAGAAACAAGUGAGGACCCUGAAGUUGAGGUGACUAUUGAAGAUGAUGAUUAUUCUCCACCGUCUAAGAGACCAAAGGCCAAUGAGCUACCGCAGCCACCAGUCCCGGAACCCGCCAAUGCUGGGAAGCGGAAAGUGAGGGAGUUCAACUUCGAGAAAUGGAAUGCUCGCAUCACUGAUCUACGUAAACAAGUUGAAGAAUUGUUUGAAAGGAAAUAUGCUCAAGCCAUAAAAGCCAAAGGUCCGGUGACGAUCCCGUACCCUCUUUUCCAGUCUCAUGUUGAAGAUCUUUAUGUAGAAGGACUUCCUGAAGGAAUUCCUUUUAGAAGGCCAUCUACUUACGGAAUUCCUCGCCUGGAGAGGAUAUUACUUGCAAAGGAAAGGAUUCGUUUUGUGAUUAAGAAACAUGAGCUUCUGAAUUCAACACGUGAAGAUUUACAGCUUGAUAAGCCAGCUUCAGGAGUAAAGGAAGAAUGGUAUGCCAGAAUCACUAAAUUAAGAAAGAUGGUGGAUCAGCUUUUCUGCAAAAAAUUUGCGGAAGCCUUGGGGAGCACUGAAGCCAAGGCUGUACCGUACCAAAAAUUUGAGGCACACCCGAAUGAUCUGUACGUGGAAGGACUGCCAGAAAACAUUCCUUUCCGAAGUCCCUCAUGGUAUGGAAUCCCAAGGCUGGAAAAAAUCAUUCAAGUGGGCAAUCGAAUUAAAUUUGUUAUUAAAAGACCAGAACUUCUGACUCACAGUACCACUGAAGUUACUCAGCCAAGAACGAAUACACCAGUCAAAGAAGAUUGGAAUGUCAGAAUUACCAAGCUACGGAAGCAAGUGGAAGAGAUUUUUAAUUUGAAAUUUGCUCAAGCUCUUGGACUCACCGAGGCAGUAAAAGUACCAUAUCCUGUGUUUGAAUCAAACCCGGAGUUCUUGUAUGUGGAAGGCUUGCCAGAGGGGAUUCCCUUCCGAAGCCCUACCUGGUUUGGAAUUCCACGACUUGAAAGGAUCGUCCGCGGGAGUAAUAAAAUCAAGUUCGUUGUUAAAAAACCUGAACUAGUUAUUUCCUACUUGCCUCCUGGGAUGGCUAGUAAAAUAAACACUAAAGCUUUGCAGUCCCCCAAAAGACCACGAAGUCCUGGGAGUAAUUCAAAGGUUCCUGAAAUUGAGGUCACCGUGGAAGGCCCUAAUAACAACAAUCCUCAAACCUCAGCUGUUCGAACCCCGACCCAGACUAACGGUUCUAACGUUCCCUUCAAGCCACGAGGGAGAGAGUUUUCCUUUGAGGCCUGGAAUGCCAAAAUCACGGACCUAAAACAGAAAGUUGAAAAUCUCUUCAAUGAGAAAUGUGGGGAAGCUCUUGGCCUUAAACAAGCUGUGAAGGUGCCGUUCGCGUUAUUUGAGUCUUUCCCGGAAGACUUUUAUGUGGAAGGCUUACCUGAGGGUGUGCCAUUCCGAAGACCAUCGACUUUUGGCAUUCCGAGGCUGGAGAAGAUACUCAGAAACAAAGCCAAAAUUAAGUUCAUCAUUAAAAAGCCCGAAAUGUUUGAGACGGCGAUUAAGGAGAGCACCUCCUCUAAGAGCCCUCCCAGAAAAAUAAAUUCAUCACCCAAUGUUAAUACUACUGCAUCAGGUGUUGAAGACCUUAACAUCAUUCAGGUGACAAUUCCAGAUGAUGAUAAUGAAAGACUCUCGAAAGUUGAAAAAGCUAGACAGCUAAGAGAACAAGUGAAUGACCUCUUUAGUCGGAAAUUUGGUGAAGCUAUUGGUAUGGGUUUUCCUGUGAAAGUUCCCUACAGGAAAAUCACAAUUAACCCUGGCUGUGUGGUAGUUGAUGGCAUGCCCCCGGGGGUGUCCUUCAAAGCCCCCAGCUACCUGGAAAUCAGCUCCAUGAGAAGGAUCUUAGACUCUGCCGAGUUUAUCAAAUUCACGGUCAUUAGACCAUUUCCAGGACUUGUGAUUAAUAACCAGCUGGUUGAUCAGAGUGAGUCAGAAGGCCCCGUGAUACAAGAAUCAGCUGAACCAAGCCAGUUGGAAGUUCCAGCCACAGAAGAAAUAAAAGAGACUGAUGGAAGCUCUCAGAUCAAGCAAGAACCAGACCCCACGUGGUAGACCUCUUCCCUCCUAGGCUUAAAGUAUCAGUGGUUGAGAAGAGCUUUUCGGACCUGUUACUACCCCAAGCUGUGUAAUAUACUUGUAUAACAGAAAUACCUUCUAUACAAACCUUUUUUUCUACUUUUAGAUAGAAAUGUCUACUUUUUCAGCAGUUCUGUGAAUUAAAGAGCAGAGUGACUGUGGGUCUGGAAUGGCUGGUGUACUUGGGAAUGUACUAUCAGGAUUUUACAGCAAUGCUGGGAAAUGACAGGGAAAAUGACAGGAAUGAAUCUCACCAGAUUUUUUAUGUACUCAGCAGAGCCUUGAGUUACGGUGUUUAUUUUCCAAUCAAGUGAAGAUAUCUCCUACUUCUCCUACUGGAACAUCUCAGCUUCUGCAGUGAAGAAAAAUUCCUGUGAUAGUUCAGUUCUUUAGUUUUUCUAUUUGAAAAAAAAAAAUCAUUUAAAUGAUCCUUUGUUCACGGCUCUCCUUAAUGACUGAGUGAACAGUUCCUAUCUGUAUAUUUGACUAAACCUUUUCCUAAGCUAUCUCUCAUGGUUCCUAUGUUUUUUUAUCAUAAUUAAAAGCAAAACCAUCUGGAUCACCUAACAGUCAGAGGUCAGUAUCUCAGCGUGUGAAUUAUAGAGGAAAUACAGAGAGAACCUCUUCCACUUUUACUUUUCGUCCAAAUAAAAUGCAUGGUGUACCAGAAGUUGAAGAUCGGGUUGAGGAUUGGGGCUAGCUCGAUGACACUAAGGCCCCAACAUCGCGGGACCUGCUGUGGCGCGGAUUCUUAGGAACGCUGUUCUAGCCGGCCCCCUCUCCAGGGGUCGCCGUGGCCGGCAUUAUUUCCUAGUUCUUCUUGUAACCCUGAGGUGCCAGCGCGGGGAGUGAGGAGGGGUCAGGGGGCUAAGGAUGCAACCUCUGACGUUCUGCGCCUUCCUAGGAGAGUCUUACAUGUGUUGAGAUUUCACAAGCAAUGCGAGUUGUAAAAUACCAGCUCUACAAGAAGCUAGGCUCUGUGACGGCAUAGUUUUCAGUAGCUUUAUCACAAUAUUCACAAUGGAGAAUUAUAUGACAUGGUAGCAGAAAUAGGCCCUUUUAUGUGUUGCUUCUAUUUUACCUCAAAUUGUAGAUAUAGGGUAAUCAAUAAAAUCCAUCCAUGCCUUUCACACACUAA